GCACGCUGGGACGUCUCGCUGGCGGGAGGCCACGGGCUUUCCACAGCGCGGGGGAACGGGAGGCUGCAGGAUGGUCAAGCUGACGGCGGAGCUGAUCGAGCAGGCGGCGCAGUACACCAACGCGGUGCGCGACCGGGAGCUGGACCUCCGGGGGUAUAAAAUUCCCGUCAUUGAAAAUCUAGGUGCUACGUUAGACCAGUUUGAUGCUAUUGAUUUUUCUGACAAUGAGAUCAGGAAACUGGAUGGUUUUCCUUUGUUGAGAAGACUGAAAACAUUGUUAGUGAACAACAACAGAAUAUGCCGUAUAGGUGAGGGACUUGAUCAGGCUCUGCCCUGUCUGACAGAACUCAUUCUCACCAAUAAUAGUCUCGUGGAACUGGGUGAUCUGGACCCUCUGGCAUCUCUCAAAUCGCUGACUUACCUAAGUAUCCUAAGAAAUCCGGUAACCAAUAAGAAGCAUUACAGAUUGUAUGUGAUUUAUAAAGUUCCGCAAGUCAGAGUACUGGAUUUCCAGAAAGUGAAACUAAAAGAGCGUCAGGAAGCAGAGAAAAUGUUCAAGGGCAAACGGGGUGCACAGCUUGCAAAGGAUAUUGCCAGGAGAAGCAAAACUUUUAAUCCAGGUGCUGGUUUGCCAACUGACAAAAAGAAAGGUGGGCCAUCUCCAGGGGAUGUAGAAGCAAUCAAGAAUGCCAUAGCAAAUGCUUCAACUCUGGCUGAAGUGGAGAGGCUGAAGGGGUUGCUGCAGUCUGGUCAGAUCCCUGGCAGAGAACGCAGAUCAGGGCCCACUGAUGAUGGUGAAGAAGAGAUGGAAGAAGACACAGUCACAAACGGGUCCUGAGCAGUGAGGCAGAUGUAUAAUAAUAGGCCCUCUUGGAACAAGUCUUGCUUUUCGAACAUGGUAUAAUAGCCUUGUUUGUGUUAGCAAAGUGGAAUCUAUCAGCAUUGUUGAAAUGCUUAAGACUGCUGCUGAUAAUUUUGUAAUAUAAGUUUUGAAAUCUAAAUGUCAAUUUUCUACAAAUUAUAAAAAUAAACUCCACUCACUAUGCUACCAA